CUGCUGUCUCUGCACGGGUGGCCAGAGCCACACAGCCCUUUCUUUAAGUCAGGAGUUGCCCUGUCAGAGCACAAGGCAAGAAGGAAGUGGUAAAGGGACGGAGGGGAAGCCCUGAGAGGACUGAGAGGAUGGGAAAUUCUCUGCUGAGAGAAAACAGGUUUUGCCUUCUCCCAAGAAUCAUGGUGAGCAGCUGAUGGAGAAUAGCUGAAAGGUGGAAAGACUUUACCAAGGAAGGUCUAUAUAAUAGGUUACCACCUAAGAAAUGAAACAACUUUCUGAAAGCCCGGGAAGGAGAUGCUCUCCUGAGCUCCUCAUGCUCCACAAGGAGGUCAAAAUCACCACCCUCUUUCAGCCACUAUUUUAAGUUUGAAAUAAACAGCAAGCUUCCUGCCACCUUGAGUCUUCCUUUGAUGUGCACUCCCUGCAAGCAGGUAAGCAGAGGUCAUCUAGAUUAAAUAGGCACAGAACUCAGAUUUACUUUCUGGACCUCAGCCUCUUUAUUUUAAGUAGAAAUAAUAAUACAAUAUCUACCUUAGAGAGUUCUAGUGUGUAUUGUGCUAGCAUAGUGCCUGACAUAAAGUAGGGUUCAAAAUUAGAAGAUAUUUUCUGCUUUCUUUUUCUGACCAUCAUCUUCCUUAAUAUCAAAGCCGUGCCACCAAAAUAGUGCCACCACAGACAAGGUAAUCUCUAGGGUAUAAAGUGGGGUGAUCUAGAGAGAGUAAGCGAGCCAGAGGGGGUCUUCACAGGGUUAUGUUUGGAAUCCCUGGUCUCAGUUCAUGCUACUGGAGAGUGGAACACAGGAAAAAAUGGUAGCCCACUUUUGACCACUUGCCGAAAAGAGGAUUGGUGGUCCUGUGGAAUAUCUCAUGUCCCUUCCUAAGAAUCAUGUUGUCUGAGACUUCUCUACCCUGGGUUGUCACAGCCCCUUGUCAAUCUUCUACUCUAGCAUUGUUCUAACAAUUAUAUAAAUUACUAUUUUUAUUACUAGAUAUGAGAUGCUCAAAUGUAGUGAUUGUUUCUUAUUUAUCUUUGAAUUCCUGGUUCCUGGCAUUGUUUCUGGCAUAUCACGUGCACUGAAUAAGUGCAAAAAAACUUUAAAAAAAUUUUUUUACUUUAAAAUUUUGUUUUAUGUAAGAAAAAAAACCUUUUUCCAAGGUGCACACAUCUUAUGCUAUUUGGACUUCUUAUGGUUUUUUAUUUAUUUUAAAGAAAAUUCGAUUUUAAAUCUAGAAAGCUUUUUGGUUUCUGCCAUUGCAUUCAUGCUUAAAAUUCUUUGCUCUUCCUAAGAUAAGACAAAUCAACUCACAUAAGUUUUGAUUUUGUUAUUUUACAUUUGGCAACAUAUAUUCAAUAUAUGGUGUCAGAUGUAAAUUUUUUUCCAAAUAGUUGAUCAGUUUGCCCAACAUCUUUAUUUCUAUGAUGAUUUAAAAGGUCUCCCUUGAACCAAGUGCAGUGGCAUGCACCUGUAGUCCCAGCUACUCAGGAGGCUGAGGCAGGAGGAUUGCUUGAGCCCAGGAGUUUGAGGGCAGCCUGAACAACAUAGCAAGACCCAGUCUUAAAAAUAAAUUCAUUAAAAUAAUUAAAUAAAAUGUUUCCGUUAACGUAUUCAAAAGUCUUGUAUAUAUUGGUAUCUAAUUUUCAUUGUCACCCCAACACCCAGUUAUCAUCUAGUCAGCAUACCCCCCCAACCGUGUCUCUCCAGAUCAAAUAAGCUAAGAAGUCAGGGAAAUUUUGCACAGAAUAGAAUGGCACUCAUCCCUUCAUGAGAGGAGCUCAGUCUCAGAGGAAGAGACCUGCCAGCAGCAAACCCAGCUUUUCCCCCUUAGUGGCUGUGGAUCCUCAGACCAGUUGCCUAGCAUUUUGGGCCUCAGUUUCCUCAUUAGUAUAAAAAAUAUAAUGAUAAUAUCUAUCUUAUGGAUUUAUUCUGGGAUUAAAUGAAAUAUAACACACAAAAUGAUUGGCAUAUAGUAAGUAGUGUUUAAGUGUUAGUUUCUUUAUCCUCAUACUCCCAAUUCCCAACAAGUGGGAAGAUGGGUAUACAGAAAUCUAACCCAAACAAUGAACCAAUUUAUUUUCUUUAUUCAAUCCUUUUCUUCUCCUUCUGUCCCUUGUUCUGGGCCUCCAUGCUUUCUGUGAAAGAUGGUGUGAUUUACACAAGACAAAGCCAGUACCUUUCCCCAUUACUUGUGCAUAGCUCCUGGAACUGCACCAAAGAGAUGGUAGCUGAGGACCUCAGGCCUCUCUCUGGACACGGAUACUCUCAAGGGUCAUGACGAGGAUCCCUGGAUAUUUGGGAUCAGAUGAUUUAGGAUCACUUGUUCAUGGAGGUUGGAGAACAUCAGUGGGCUGUUGCUGUGGCAAUGGAGAGCAUGUCAGAUCAAAGGUAGCUUGCGACAUGUGCUUGAGGAAACAGUAUUAACAUGUGUGAGGGCAACCAGUCAAUUUCUGAGUUACACACAAAUAGCAGAAAUGAGGAAAGUCGGAAAAAUUAUGAAAAGAAGUGACAGGCCUGUUUAGGAAAUACUUAGCCUGUUUCUGAUAUGUUGAGUUUCAGGCGGCAGCAGAACACUCAAGAGAUGCCUUGGAAUGUGAGAAUGCAAAGCCCCAAACAGAGAACAUCCAGAUGCUGGGAUCACCAUAUCGCUGAAGGGUGUUUCUGCCUUCCAUGGAAAAAAAUACUCAUUUUUGAAAAGAGGCAAGAUUCCCAAAACGAAAAUGAAAGAAUGUCAUCUACUCCCAUCCAGCAGGACAAUGUUGACCAGACCUACUCAGAGGAGCUGUGCUAUACCCUCAUCAAUCAUCGGGUUCUCUGUACAAGGCCAUCAGGGAACUCUGCUGAAGAGUACUAUGAGAAUGUUCCCUGCAAAGCUGAGAGACCCAGAGAGUCCUUGGGAGGAACUGAGACUGAGUAUUCACUUCUACAUAUGCCUUCUACAGACCCCAGGCAUGCCCGAUCCCCAGAAGAUGAAUAUGAACUUCUCAUGCCUCACAGAAUCUCCUCUCACUUUCUGCAACAGCCACGUCCACUUAUGGCCCCUUCUGAGACUCAGUUUUCCCAUUUAUAGUGAAGUGGCUGGACUAGCAUUUGUUUAGCACCAACAAAUAAAAGGUGGGAUGGGGGAUCUGCCUGAAGCAGGGAUGGGACACAAAGUCCCUCCAGCUUAUCUCCCACAACAACCCUUUCCCUGCAGAGCAUGGUUUGUAUACCACAAGCCCUCUUAGCACGCAAAAGCCAAAAUCUAAAGAUCAACCAUUUAUCCUGAACAACACCAUUUGAGAAAGAGGUAACCAUCUUUGGUUCUACAUGGUUUGGAGAGUAUAGUGGUAGGAGGGGCUCCCUGAUUCCCCUAAAGCUAUGCACACCACAAGGGGCUCUGCUCUUCUGUCUGGGAUCUUCUUAUAAAGUGUUCCCAUGAUCAUUCUCUAAAGUCACAAGGAAGCUUUACUCAUCAUACUAAGUGUGCCCAAGGGGGAGUUCACUCAUUACUGUGACCUUCCAGCUCAGUCCCCACCCAUGGGAGCCUGUGUUGCUCCUCUCACUCCAUGUGUCUAAGUCAUGUCUUUUACAUAGUGUCCUUUGACCUGUUGGCCCCCAUGGUCUGGUUAGUUAUGUGAGUUGAAUCAAGAGGCUCUAGGCCAGAUGUUUACAUAAUUUUAACCUAUAUGAUUUUAUUUUUAACUUUGUAUUUCUCCCUAGAAAUCUUAAUAAGACAAUUAUGCCAUCAGACAAUGUUAAGAAGAACGAUCCUUGGAGAUCCCGUAAUCCCACUACCCUUCUUUGGCUCAGAGAGGAUAAUUUGCCUAAUGAUACAUUAAAGUUAGUGGCAAAACUUAAUUUGGAGCCUGAUUUCCUACUGACUUCCAAUUUAGUGCUCCCCCAGUAUGCUAAAUAGAAAGCCCUCUGCAAUAUAUUAAAUGUAUACUAAAUGUAUAUAUUUAAUAAUGUCAUGUAUAAAAUAUGAAUAAAAUGUCCACAUAGGAAAUUAACACAUA